CGAAAAUCUUAAAGGCCUUUCCCCUUCCCUCACUGGGCUCAAACAACAGCGGGAGCCGCCCUGCCACUCCCCGUCGCGGUCCAGGGGAGCAGGCUAGCUGACUGAGGGCGAUCAUGGGCCCCAAAAGGUCUGCGGGCGACGCGGGCUCCCACCUCAGGGCGCAGCGACUGGGGCGAGAGGUGCCGGCAGCCCCCAAGCCAGCCCCGCGGCAAGGAGCCAGAGAGACGCGCCCUCCCCCUCCUCCCACGCAAGCCUCACACAGCGGGGCGGGCCAGACGCGGGAGAAAGGGGCGCGCUCGCCCCGCCUGGGGAACCGGGGCCUCUCCCGGGCAGGCUCGCCUUUGUCCCGGGACUCUGGGCGCCUCCUCUCCGCCCUCGCCCUGCCCCGUGAGGCCGCCACUGGGCGCCUCACCGUGAUGUUGCAGUGGAGCGUGAGCUGCGGCGGCGGCUCCUGGUUCUUGUGGAAGAUAGAGGCCAACAACUUCAGCUUGGCCUUGAACCCUCACACGGACAUUUUACUCUCACCUCUGGCGGGAGGGGCGCGGAAGAGUUCAUUAGUUUCUGUUUGCUCUCAGUUAAUAUCCAGCUCAAUAGAUUGUGUAAGUAGAAUACCCCCAAACUGAAAGUCACCUACAUAAAAUAUAGUGAAAAAUAUGUCACCCACUUAAACUAUAGUUGAAAAUAUGUACUCAUUAGUUUUGUGUAGCCAACACUGGAUAAUGGGUAAGGGGAAAGGAUCCCAGGGCUAGACUGCCUGGGUUCAAGUUCCGAUUUCCUGCUGGCUGUGAAAUACUUGACAGCGUUCAGCCUCUGUUUCUUUUCUUUUUUUUUUUUUUAGCUUAAUCCCAAAUAUGAUAGUAAGUCUCAGUUUCUUGAUCUGAAAAACAGAAAUUAUUCAAUGACAGUCUAUGUGAAAACUUUAAAGUUUUCAAAGCCACUAUCUAGCUUAGGAAAGUCCUCAGCUUUAGGGGUUAAAGUUUUUAAAACCACUGCCUGGUUCAGGAAAGCCCUCAGCUGUAGCCAUUAUUAGCUAUGAUUAUUAUUGUGGUGGCUACACAUACAUUAAUGAGGCAGGAAAAUGCUCAAGGAUAACAAGCAAGUAUCCAGAUUAUCUCAUCAGACCAAGACAGAUGCAUAUGCAUGCAUGAUCAUGUUUUAGCUCAGAGCCAUUUGUCUAAAAGGCUCUUGAACUCAGAGGCCCAGGAGUAUCAACUUUGCUUUGCAGUGGAGCCAUCGCUUUUGUUAAUCAAUGAAAUUGACAUAAUGCUCUUCUUUUUUUUUUCC